GUCUAGGGCGCUGCGCGGCGCAGCGAAAAUGGCGGCUUCCAGGUGGGCGCGCAAGGCCGUGGUCCUGCUUUGUGCCUCUGACCUGCUGCUGCUGCUGCUACUGCUACCACCGCCUGGGUCCUGCGCGGCCGAAGGCUCGCCCGGGACGCCCGACGAGUCUACCCCACCUCCCCGGAAGAAGAAGAAGGAUAUUCGCGAUUACAAUGAUGCAGACAUGGCGCGUCUUCUGGAGCAAUGGGAGAAAGAUGAUGACAUUGAAGAAGGAGAUCUUCCAGAGCACAAGAGACCUUCAGCACCUGUCGACUUCUCAAAGAUAGACCCAAGCAAGCCUGAAAGCAUAUUGAAAAUGACGAAAAAAGGGAAGACUCUCAUGAUGUUUGUCACUGUAUCAGGAAGCCCUACUGAGAAGGAGACAGAGGAAAUUACGAGCCUCUGGCAGGGCAGCCUUUUCAAUGCCAACUAUGACGUCCAGAGGUUCAUUGUGGGAUCAGACCGUGCUAUCUUCAUGCUUCGCGAUGGGAGCUACGCCUGGGAGAUCAAGGACUUUUUGGUCGGUCAAGACAGGUGUGCUGAUGUAACUCUGGAGGGCCAGGUGUACCCCGGCAAAGGAGGAGGAAGCAAAGAGAAAAAUAAAACAAAGCAAGACAAGGGCAAAAAAAAGAAGGAAGGAGAUCUGAAAUCUCGGUCUUCCAAGGAAGAAAAUCGAGCUGGGAAUAAAAGAGAAGACCUGUGAUGGGGCAGCAGUGACGCGCUGUGGGGGGACAGGUGGACGUGGAGAGCUCUUUGCCCAGCUCCUGGGGUGGGAGUGGUCUCAGGCAACUGCACACCGGAUGACAUUCUAGUGUCUUCUAGAAAGGGUCUGCCACAUGACCAGUUUGUGGUCAAAGAAUUACUGCUUAAUAGGCUUCAAGUAAGAAGACAGAUGUUUUCUAAUUAAUACUGGACACUGACAAAUUCAUGUUUACUAUAAAAUCUCCUUACAUGGAAAUGUGACUGUGUUGCUUUUUCCCAUUUACACUUGGUGAGUCAUCAACUCUACUGAGAUUCCACUCCCCUCCAAGCACCUGCUGUGAUUGGGUGGCCUGCUCUGAUCAGAUAGCAAAUUCUGAUCAGAGAAGACUUUAAAACUCUUGACUUAAUUGAGUAAACUCUUCAUGCCAUAUACAUCAUUUUCAUUAUGUUAAAGGUAAAAUAUGCUUUGUGAACUCAGAUGUCUGUAGCCAGGAAGCCAGGGUGUGUAAAUCCAAAAUCUAUGCAGGAAAUGCGGAGAAUAGAAAAUAUGUCACUUGAAAUCCUAAGUAGUUUUGAAUUUCUUUGACUUGAAUCUUACUCAUCAGUAAGAGAACUCUUGGUGUCUGUCAGGUUUUAUGUGGUCUGUAAAGUUAGGGGUUCUGUUUUGUUUCCUUAUUUAGGAAAGAGUACUGCUGGUGUCGAGGGGUUAUAUGUUCCAUUUAAUGUGACAGUUUUAAAGGAUUUAAGUAGGGAAUCAGAGUCCUUUGCAGAGUGUGACAGACGACUCAAUAACCUCAUUUGUUUCUAAACAUUUUUCUUUGAUAAAGUGCCUAAAUCUGUGCUUUCGUAUAGAGUAACAUGAUGUGCUACUGUUGAUGUCUGAUUUUGCCGUUCAUGUUAGAGCCUACUGUGAAUAAGAGUUAGAACAUUUAUAUACAGAUGUCAUUUCUAAGAACUAAAAUUCUUUGGGAAAAACCCUCAAUUGUGAUUUUAAUAAAUUAAAAGUAGCACAUUACAUGGUUAGAAAAUGUCAGUGUUAAAGAAUGGUACAAAGUGAAAAGUGUAUCCCUCUCUUGCCGCCGGUGGUAGCUUGUCCCAGUGGAAGCUGCUGUUAACAAUUUGUGCCCCCACAUCCCCCUCCCUGCCCAUCCACCAAAAAAAAGUACAUUUACUUAUGUAAAUGUACUUAUGGUGAUGUAUGUUUGUUUUGGCCUCACAGCAUCUGUUUCCCCUUAAUUUGGUAGCUGCUCACAUUUCCCUCGAAAGAACCACACCCUCUGCAUUCUCAGUUCUCUGCUUUGGAUGGGACAUUUGCCCUGCAGUCCCCCCACCCUCCAGGCCAUGCCCUCUCCAGGGUGAGGCCUGUGUGAUCUACCGUACUAGGGUACUAGGCCCUGAAAGAGGCUUUUCUUGUUCCUCCUGCAUCUUGAACCUGGAGCGGGAGCUGUUGUAGGCCCCGCCCUUGGAGAAGAGAACUGUCUGACAGUGGGGAGAGAGCGCCACACCCUGGUGGCAUAAACGAGUCCCUGAAUCAUGCCGUGGCUGAACCAAGCCCUGUCUGUGGGCUUUUUCUGUUGUACUCAGGGCAGUUUGAUGGGGUUACUGUCCUGCAUAGCCAUAAUGGCCCAGUAUAAAGCAGCUGUUUUGAUGAGAUAAUUGCUUUAAUUAAGCAAAAGGUAGCAAAGCUUUCACUCCGCCCUGUACCUUCUGUUUCCACUUAGGAGCCUUCCCAUGUCAGAAUGUGCAGAUCUGUCUCAUUGUUUCCUGUGCAGUGUGCCCCCACUUCACCCAGUAGUUUCUGUGUGUCUGUUAUGUACUAGGUACUACAAGGUGCCAGGACGGUGUAGAUACAGCCUCUGCUAUCGUAAAACUCAAUGAUUCGGUGGGGGAAGACAAAUGUCAGUAAUGUACAAAGUAAAAUGGCAGCUGUUAGAAGUAUGAAAGGGGCAGGGUAGGGGGAGGUAGAAUCUUCCCUGACCAGGUUAAGAAAACCAGAGGCCUUCUCUGAGGGCAAGAGGAGGAGAGGAGAAAUAGAGUAAGGCAGGCAGAGGAAACAGUCUGAGCUAAGACCCUGUGGCUAGAAGUGGCAGAGGGAGAGGCAGCAGGAAGGCCAGCGGGGAGGCUGGGGCCCAGUGCAGGCCCAGGUUGGAGGAGCGUAGCACAUGGAGUUUGGUAGGAGUUUGGGACGCCCUGGUGGAUCUUAAUUGUGAUGGGGUGGGUGUGAAAGGCAGUCCAGGUUGCACUGGUUGCACAGGAGAAGUGAUCAGAAGAGGACCCCAGCAGGUGUGAGCCGUGAGCUGGGAGGUGCUUCAGUAGUGCAGGCCAUAGCUGAAGGUGUCCUACAUCAGCAGGGUGAUGGUGAGGUUUGAACCACUGUUUCACUGCAUAGUCCCUGCUGAUGGACACUUGAGUGUUCAGAUUUUUUGCUGGUAUAUUCAGUGCUGCAGUGGACAUUUUCAUACAAAAUAUUUCGGUACACUUUUGUUUAUAUCUGAAAGGUAAAUUCCUAGCAGUAGAAUUAUUAGAGCAAACGGAAUUUAACAUUUUGGUGUGUAUUGCCAAAUUGCCCUCCCAAGUGGUUUAGUCAGCUUACCCUUGCCAACAAUAGAUCUAUCCUUGCCAGCCUUGGGCAUCACAUUUACCAGUUUAAUAGAUUGUAAAACCAUAUCUUAAUUGGCUACCCUGAAGCCACCAUACUGGAGAGGCUGCGUACAGUGUUUCACGUAGAGAGAGGGAUACCCAGGAGGCCCACCUGCUCCAACCCCAGCUGCAUGAGUCUUCCCAGCCCAGGCACAGACAUGUGGAUAAGAUUUAAACAUUUCCAGCCCCAGCCUUCAAGCAAUCCUAGUUGACACUGAGGGGAGCCAACAUAAGCUGAGCUGAGAAACAGUCUGCCCAGUCUGCAGAUUCAUGAGCAAAAGAAAUGUUGGGCUGGGUACAGUGGCUCACGCCUGUAAUCCCAGUACUUUGGGAGGCCGAGGUGGGUGGAUCAGUUGAGGUCAGGAGUUUGAGACCAGCCUGGCCAACAUGGUGAAGCCCUGUCUCUACUAAAAAUUAGCCGAGUGUGGUGGUGCGGGCCUGUAAUCCCAGCUACUCAGGUGGCUGAGGCAGGAGAAUGGCUUGAACCCGGGAGGCGGAGGUUGCAGUGAGCCAAGAUCAGGCCACUGCACUCCAGCCUGGAUGACGGGAUGAGACUCUGUCUCAAAAAAACGAAACAAAAAUUUUUUAAGAGAAAUGUCAUUUGUUUUUGUUUUUGAGACAGGGUCUCACUCUGUUGCCCUCACUAGAGUGCAGUAGGAUCACGGCUCACUGAAGUCUCUACCUACCGGCUCAAUUGAUCUUCCCACCACAGCCUCCCAAAUAGCUGGGAGAAAUGUCCUGUUUUUAAUGAAUUUGUCUUCCUUUUUGUCUUGUUUGUUUUAAUAUCUAGUGAUCUAAUAAAUUUGGAUGAUAUCUUUUGACUAUCAA